GCACUUCCCGGGCCCGGCCGGCCUGGAUGGACUAGCCGGGGCCAUGGCCGGCGCGGCGGCGGAGUCAGGGCGGGAGCUGUGGACCUUCGCGGGUUCCCGGGACCCGAGCGCACCGCGGCUAGCCUACGGCUACGGCCCGGGCAGCCUGCGCGAGCUGCGGGCGCGCGAGUUCAGCCGCCUGGCAGGAACUGUCUAUCUUGACCAUGCAGGUGCCACCUUGUUCUCCCAGAGCCAGCUCGAAAGCUUCACUAGUGAUCUCAUGGAAAACACUUAUGGUAAUCCUCACAGCCAGAACAUCAGCAGCAAGCUCACCCAUGACACUGUGGAGCAGGUGCGCUACAGAAUCCUGGCGCACUUCCACACCACCGCAGAAGACUACACUGUGAUCUUCACUGCCGGGAGCACGGCUGCUCUCAAACUGGUGGCAGAGGCCUUUCCAUGGGUGUCCCAGGGCCCAGAGAGCAGUGGGAGUCGCUUCUGUUACCUCACCGACAGCCACACCUCCGUAGUGGGUAUGCGGAACGUGACCAUGGCUAUAAAUGUCAUAUCCACCCCGGUCAGGCCAGAGGACCUGUGGUCUGCAGAGGAACGUAGUGCUUCAGCCAGCAACCCAGACUGCCAGCUGCCGCAUCUCUUCUGCUACCCAGCUCAGAGUAACUUUUCUGGAGUCAGAUACCCCCUGUCCUGGAUAGAAGAGGUCAAGUCUGGGCGGUUGCACCCUGUGAGCACGCCUGGGAAGUGGUUUGUGCUGCUGGAUGCAGCCUCCUACGUGAGCACCUCGCCUUUGGACCUGUCAGCUCACCAGGCCGACUUUGUCCCCAUCUCCUUCUAUAAGAUCUUCGGGUUUCCUACAGGCCUGGGCGCUCUGCUGGUCCAUAAUCGUGCGGCUCCUCUACUGAGGAAGACCUACUUUGGAGGAGGGACAGCCUCUGCGUACCUAGCAGGAGAAGACUUCUACAUCCCGAGGCAGUCGGUAGCUCAGAGGUUUGAAGAUGGCACCAUCUCAUUCCUUGAUGUUAUCGCGCUAAAACAUGGAUUUGACACCCUAGAGCGCCUCACAGGUGGAAUGGAGAAUAUAAAGCAGCACACCUUCACCUUGGCUCAGUAUACCUACGUGGCCCUGUCCUCUCUCCAGUACCCCAAUGGAGCCCCUGUGGUGCGGAUUUACAGCGAUUCUGAGUUCAGCAGCCCUGAGGUUCAGGGCCCAAUCAUCAAUUUUAAUGUGCUGGAUGACAAAGGGAACAUCAUUGGUUACUCCCAGGUGGACAAAAUGGCCAGUCUUUACAACAUCCACCUGCGAACUGGCUGCUUCUGUAACACUGGGGCCUGCCAGAGGCACCUGGGCAUAAGCAACGAGAUGGUCAGGAAGCAUUUUCAGGCUGGUCAUGUCUGUGGGGACAAUAUGGACCUCAUAGAUGGGCAGCCCACAGGAUCUGUGAGGAUUUCAUUUGGAUACAUGUCGACGCUGGAUGAUGUCCAGGCCUUUCUUAGGUUCAUCAUAGACACUCGCCUGCACUCAUCAGGGGACUGGCCUGUCCCUCAGGCCCAUGCUGACACCGGGGAGACUGGAGCCCCAUCAGCAGACAGCCAGGCUGAUGUUAUACCUGCUGUCAUGGGCAGACGUAGCCUCUCGCCUCAGGAAGAUGCCCUCACAGGCUCCAGGGUUUGGAACAACUCGUCUACUGUGAAUGCUGUGCCUGUGGCCCCACCUGUGUGUGAUGUCGCCAGAACCCAGCCGACUCCUUCAGAGAAAGCUGCAGGAGUCCUGGAGGGGGCCCUUGGGCCACAUGUUGUCACUAACCUUUAUCUCUAUCCAAUCAAAUCCUGUGCUGCAUUUGAGGUGACCAGGUGGCCUGUAGGAAACCAAGGGCUGCUAUAUGACCGGAGCUGGAUGGUUGUGAAUCACAAUGGUGUUUGCCUGAGUCAGAAGCAGGAACCCCGGCUCUGCCUGAUCCAGCCCUUCAUCGACUUGCGGCAAAGGAUCAUGGUCAUCAAAGCCAAAGGGAUGGAGCCUAUAGAGGUGCCUCUUGAGGAAAAUAGUGAACGGACUCAGAUUCGCCAAAGCAGGGUCUGUGCUGACAGAGUAAGUACUUAUGAUUGUGGAGAAAAAAUUUCAAGCUGGUUGUCAACAUUUUUUGGCCGUCCUUGUCAUUUGAUCAAACAAAGUUCAAACUCUCAAAGGAAUGCAAAGAAGAAACAUGGAAAAGAUCAACUUCCUGGUACAAUGGCCACCCUUUCUCUGGUGAAUGAGGCACAGUAUCUGCUGAUCAACACAUCCAGUAUUUUGGAACUUCACCGGCAACUAAACACCAGUGAUGAGAAUGGAAAGGAGGAAUUAUUCUCACUGAAGGAUCUCAGCUUGCGUUUUCGUGCCAAUAUUAUUAUCAAUGGAAAAAGGGCUUUUGAAGAAGAGAAAUGGGAUGAGAUUUCAAUUGGCUCUUUGCGUUUCCAGGUUUUGGGGCCUUGUCACAGAUGCCAGAUGAUUUGCAUCGACCAGCAAACUGGGCAACGAAACCAGCAUGUUUUCCAAAAACUUUCUGAGAGUCGUGAAACAAAGGUGAACUUUGGCAUGUACCUGAUGCAUGCAUCAUUGGAUUUAUCCUCCCCAUGUUUCCUGUCUGUAGGAUCUCAGGUGCUCCCUGUGUUGAAAGAGAAUGUGGAAGGUCAUGAUUUACCUGCAUCUGAGAAACACCAGGAUGUUACCUCCUAAAAAAAAUUUUUAGCAUAAAGUUUCUCUUUUACAGUGAUCUCUAUUAUUGUUAAGAUCUGCAACUUGGUUCAGUAGAACUUGAUGUUUUGAAUAAGGAGAGCUCUUUUUCUUUAGAGGCAGGGAAUGCUCUCACCUGCUUCCUUCUGCCUUUGACUUCUCACCCUGCAAAUUUGCACUGGCUGUGCUCAGGAGAGCACUUCUGAGGCCUCAGGAACGAAUGCUGCACCCACAUCCAGUGAGGCUCCUGUAGGUAUUUGAAGUAUAAUCACUUGUAAUCAGAUGAAAUUUUUAAUGAAGUUCACUGGGAAGAUUGAACUUACUGCGGGUCCCUAUUUUGCCAUUUUCUCACAUUGUUACUUUGUUUUUAGAGAGCAUCUUUGGAUCUCUCCAACCCGUUUGUAGUGAGGAAGGGAGUCUAUGCCCAGUGAUCCUGGGUAUGAGAAGGUGCUCCUCUCCUCCCAUGUACAUGAUGGUGUGGGUUUAUGCUCAGGGGCCCAGAGGGUAACUUGUGACCACAUUCCUUGAGGGGAGUUUCUACCAGAAUAUUUAUAUUCUGAGCAAAGGCACAGGCCAGCAAUUCCUUUCCUGUUGCUUCCCAUCCCUGGCCUCCGUCCUCAUCCCCCACUGAGUUGAUGCACUGAGGAUGGCUCACGAGCCUGAAGUUACACUCAGUGAUGGCUGUGCUUAUGCAGGUUGUCAUCCUCCCCUCCACAAGCCCACAGGAUGGUGUUGGUCCAUCACCCGAGAGCCUCCAAAUCCUAUCGAGGGAGGAACUUUGGCAUUCAGGAAUCCUGUCUGUAUCAUCUUUGACCACUGCUCCUGCAGCCUCCAGAUGAAAAUGUCCAGUGAGGAAAUCUCAUUCUCUAAUGAAGUUACCCAUCCCGCUGAGUUUCUAAGAAGUUUCUCCCUGUGCGGAGCUUGUGUGUGCCUUAUCUGCUUCUGCAUGACUUCCAGCCUGGGGUCUUACCCUGUCCUCUGGAGCAAUGCAGAGUGAGUACAUCCACUCCACAUUCAUUCUGCUGGCGUCCUUCUGAAGCCUGCUGUCCAUGUGUGAACCCAGUCCCUUCAUCAUCUUCCCCCUGGAUGGUUGUAUUUUUCCAGUCACUUCUCCCCCAAAUGUCUGCCUGCUGCAGCCCACUGCAUCUUUUGAAAGCCUGUGCCACCCCAUCUCUCCUGCUGCUCAGUUGGAGAGCAGGCUCCAGGCUCAGGCUUCCCUAAUGUAUCUGUUCAGAGCCUGUGGGAUUCAGGGUCAGUUUGUUUCAUUAUCACAUUUGUAGGACUUUGUGUUGUUCCCAGCACUAGGUGAGAUUUGAAAGAUGAGGUGUGCUCUGUUCUCAAGGAUUGUUGAGAUGGAGCCUAAUGAUUGCACACUCACGUGCUGUGAAGAGUUAAGGGUAAAAAGUACAACUCUGACUCUGGUUCCUGAGAUCACCGAAAGAAGAGGCAAAUGAAGUUAGGUGGGGUGGGGUGGGGUUUAUUGUUUUGAACUGUUUAUUAAAAACGCAACCUCUUCAAAGACUCAGCACUGCCACAUCAUAUGAGUGGACUUGUCCUCAUCAGCUAACUGAUAGGAGAACAAUGCCCUAAAGUAAUGGAUUUAUCCACCUACUCAGGCCAGUUUCAUGCAGGAGGGAACUUUCCAGAUGGCACAUUGCCCCAUUUCCAAGACCUUCCGCUGACAAAUGCAUCAUAUUAAUUAUGAUGGAAAACAAGUAAGAAGGCAUGCUCUACAAAAAUUAGGUCACUUGCCCAGGUGCGGUGGCUCACACCUGUAAUUCCAGCACUUUGGGAGGCUGACGUGGGCAGAUCAUGAGGUCAGGAGAUCGAGACCAUCCUGGCUAACACGGUGAAACCCCGUCUCUACUAAAAUACAAAAAAUUAGCUGGGCAUGGUGGCAUGCACCUGUAGUCCCAGCUACUUGGGAGGCUGAGGCAGGGGAAUCGCUUGAACCCGGGAGGCGGAGGUUGCAGUGAGCCGAGAUCAUGCCACUGCACACCGGCCUGGUGACAGAGCAAGACUCCAUCUCAAAAAAAAAAAAAAAAAAAUUAGGUCACUUUUGUCAUCAAGAAUAUGUUUUUCUUAUCCACGUCUAUGUCACCUUUUGCAGUAGAUACUUUCAUGACUGAUUUCAGGCUUUUUGUUUUUUUGAGACAGGGUCUCACUCUGUCACCCAGGCUGGAGUGCAGUGGCAUGAUCACAGAUCAUUGCAGCCUUGACCUCUUGGGCUCAAGCGAUUCCCCUGCCUCAGCCUCCCAAGUAGCUGGGACUACAGGCACACAUCACCACAUCCAGCUAAUUUUUUUUUUCUUUUUUUUCUUUUUGGUAGAGAUGGCAUCUCACUUUGUUGCCCAGGCUAGUUUUGAAUUCCUGGGCUCAAGCCAUCCUCCCGCCACAGCCUCCCAAAGUUCUGGGAUUACAAGUGUGAGCCACUGUGCCCAGCUUUUGAUUUCAGACAUUUUAAUGCAGAUCCUCUCCUUUACAGCACUAUUAUUUGGUUAUCUACUUAUAAUUACUGAUUUAACAUUGAUCUGUUUUCACUAGACUGUAAGCUCCAUGAGGACAAGUCCUGUGCCAGUAUAUCUCUAGUGUCAGCAGACAAUACUCAAAAUUUGUUGACAGACUAUUUAAAGCUGCCCCUAUUUUUAUCAUUAAUUGAUUGAAUAUUAAUUAAAUAUAUUUUAUUAAUUUAAAAUGAAUUUUAAAUGCAUUUUUUCUUUAGUGUCUACCUUCAAUAUUUCUUGUAUGAAGUUUCAGCUAAAAAUGUACUUUGUGUAUCUGUAGAGUGGCUUCAUAUUCAGAGUUUAUGGACAUUUAUGAUUUUAUGUCCCCUCCUUGGUUCUUAUCUCCUGGAGUUCAGCCUUAUGUGCUUCUCAAAGUGUAUAACAAAAUCAAAGACAAUGUCAUGUCCCUUGAAUUUAAUUCUAACACCAAACCUUGGUGUUAGAGUCACAAAAAGUCCUUUUUUAAAAAAACUUGGUGAGAACAGACAAUAACUUGUCUUUCUGGGCAUUCGCGUCAUGGUCCUUUUAGCCAGAAGAGAGGUUUUCUUUUGCAUAGUUUGGUGAGCAUCAAGAAUCCUUUAAGGAGGGUGGCGGUGCUGACUUCUCCCCAUUGAGAGUCAGCCUCAUCCCCUCCUCAGCCUUGUGGAUGGAGAAGAACAGGCAGUGAUAUACAUUUUCUGCUGUUGAAAGAUGUCCGCUUAUCCUUCUCUUUCAGUGAAAAGUUGCUUUUUUAUUCAAUAUGUACUGAACAGGUUCUAGAGUUUCAGAAACAAAAGAAACAGAACCAACAUUUAUAGAUCUCACUAUAGAGGCAUCACUAAUUGGGGAAAGACAGACUAGGUAAUAGUCAGAUGUGAUAUAGUAUGUUUAAGCUAUAGGAUGGCAGGUGCAUGAGUGUUGGUUGUAUUAUUCUUUAUUUUUUUGUAUGACUUAUGAUAUUCAUGAUAAUUAAAACGUUUUGGAACAAUUCA